CCUCCUUUGUUCUCCUGUGCAGGGCCCGGGAUGGUGCUCUCCCUGACGGGGCUCAUUGCCUUCUCCUUCCUGCAAGCCACCCUUGCCCUGAACCCCGAGGACCCCAACGUGUGCAGCCACUGGGAGAGCUAUGCUGUGACUGUCCAGGAAUCGUAUGCACACCCCUUCGAUCAGAUCUAUUACACACGAUGCACAGACAUCCUCAACUGGUUCAAGUGCACCAGGCACCGGAUCAGUUAUAAGACGGCGUAUCGGAGAGGCCUCCGGACCAUGUACCGGCGGAGGUCCCAGUGCUGCCCUGGCUACUAUGAGAGCGGAGACUUCUGCAUACCCCUGUGUACGGAGGAGUGUGUGCACGGCCGCUGCGUUUCCCCGGACACCUGCCACUGCGAGCCUGGCUGGGGAGGGCCCGACUGCUCCAGCGGCUGCGACAGCGACCACUGGGGGCCCCACUGCAGCAACCGGUGCCAGUGCCAGAACGGCGCCCUGUGUAACCCCAUCACAGGCGCCUGCGUGUGCGCCGCCGGCUUCCGUGGAUGGCGCUGCGAGGAGCUCUGCGCACCUGGCACCCACGGCAAGGGAUGCCAGCUGCCGUGCCAGUGCCGACACGGUGCCAGCUGCGACCCCCGCGCCGGCGAGUGCCUCUGCGCACCUGGCUACACCGGCGUCUACUGCGAGGAGCUGUGCCCUCCUGGGAGCCAUGGAGCUCACUGUGAGCUGCGCUGCCCCUGUCAGAAUGGGGGCACCUGCCACCACAUCACUGGCGAGUGUGCCUGCCCCCCAGGCUGGACGGGAGCAGUGUGUGCCCAGCCCUGCCCACCAGGGACAUUUGGCCAGAACUGCAGCCAGGAUUGUCCUUGCCACCAUGGAGGGCAGUGUGACCACGUGACUGGACAGUGCCACUGUACAGCUGGAUACAUGGGGGACAGGUGCCAAGAGGAGUGCCCCUUCGGGUCCUUCGGCUUCCAGUGCUCACAGCACUGUGACUGCCACAAUGGGGGGCAGUGUUCACCCACCACGGGUGCCUGCGAGUGUGAGCCUGGCUACAAGGGCCCACGCUGCCAGGAGCGACUGUGCCCGGAGGGCCUGCAUGGCCCAGGCUGCACCCUGCCCUGCCCCUGUGACGCUGACAACACCAUCAGCUGCCACCCAGUAACUGGAGCUUGUACCUGCCAGCCAGGCUGGUCUGGUCACCACUGCAAUGAAUCCUGCCCUGUUGGCUACUAUGGCGAUGGCUGCCAGCUGCCUUGCACCUGUCAGAAUGGCGCCGACUGCCACAGCAUCACUGGGGGCUGCACUUGUGCUCCGGGCUUCAUGGGAGAGGUCUGUGCCGUUUCCUGUGCAGCAGGGACCUAUGGCCCCAACUGCUCGUCCAUCUGUAGCUGUAACAAUGGUGGCACCUGCUCCCCAGUAGAUGGCUCCUGUACCUGCAAGGAAGGGUGGCAGGGCCUGGACUGCACCCUGCCAUGUCCCAGUGGGACGUGGGGCCUGAACUGCAACGAGAGCUGCACCUGUGCCAAUGGGGCAGCCUGCAGCCCCAUAGACGGCUCCUGCUCCUGCACUCCUGGCUGGCUGGGAGACACCUGUGAGCUGCCUUGCCCGGAUGGCACAUUUGGGCUGAACUGCAGUGAACACUGUGACUGCAGCCAUGCUGAUGGAUGUGACCCCGUCACAGGCCACUGCUGCUGCCUGGCCGGAUGGACAGGCAUCCGCUGUGACAGCACGUGUCCACCUGGCCGCUGGGGCCCCAACUGCUCUGUCUCCUGCAGCUGUGAGAAUGGAGGCUCCUGCUCCCCAGAGGAUGGGAGCUGCGAGUGUGCCCCUGGCUUCCGAGGACCCUUAUGCCAGAGAAUCUGCCCCCCUGGGUUCUAUGGCCACGGCUGCGCCCAGCCAUGCCCCCUCUGCGUGCACAGCAGCAGGCCCUGCCACCACAUCAGCGGCAUCUGUGAGUGCCUCCCAGGAUUCUCUGGAGCUCUCUGCAACCAAGUGUGUGCUGGAGGAUACUUUGGGCAGGACUGUGCCCAGCUCUGCUCCUGUGCCAACAACGGGACCUGCAGCCCUAUCGAUGGCUCCUGCCAGUGCUUUCCUGGAUGGAUUGGCAAGGACUGCUCACAGGCUUGCCCACCCGGGUUCUGGGGCCCCGCCUGCUUCCACGCAUGCAGCUGCCACAACGGGGCGAGCUGCAGCGCCGAGGACGGGGCCUGCCACUGCACCCCUGGCUGGACUGGACUCUUCUGCACACAGCGCUGCCCAGCAGCAUUUUUUGGGAAGGACUGUGGGCGCGUAUGCCAGUGUCAGAAUGGCGCCAGCUGUGACCACAUCAGUGGCAAGUGCACCUGCCGCACAGGCUUCACCGGGCAACACUGUGAGCAGAGAUGUGCCCCAGGAACCUUUGGCUAUGGGUGUCAGCAGCUAUGUGAGUGCAUGAACAACUCCACCUGUGACCAUGUCACCGGCACCUGUUACUGCAGCCCUGGCUUCAAAGGAAUCAGGUGUGACCAAGCUGCCCUCAUGAUGGAGGAGCUGAAUCCCUACACCAAGAUCAGCCCAGCACUGGGUGCAGAGCGGCACUCGGUGGGUGCUGUCACAGGCAUCAUGCUCCUGUUAUUCCUCAUUGUGGUGCUGCUGGGCCUAUUUGCCUGGCAUCGGCGGCGGCAGAAAGAGAAGGGCCGAGACCUGGCUCCCCGUGUCUCCUACACACCUGCCAUGAGGAUGACCAGCACCGACUACUCCCUCUCAGAUUUGUCUCAAAGUAGCAGCCAUGCCCACUGCUUUUCCAAUUCCAGCUACCACGCACUGGCAUGUGGGGGGCCUGCCACCAGCCAGGCCAGCACUCUGGACAGGAACAGCCCCACCAAGCUCAGUAACAAGUCCCUUGACAGAGACACAGCAGGCUGGACCCCCUACAGCUAUGUGAACGUGUUAGACUCCCAUUUCCAGAUCAGUGCCCUGGAGGCCAGGUACCCGCCCGAGGACUUCUACAUUGAACUUAGACACCUCAGCCGCCCCGCUGAGCCACACUCACCAGGUGCUUGUGGAAUGGAUAGACGUCAGAACACAUACAUUAUGGACAAAGGCUUCAAAGAUUACAUGAAAGAAUCCGUGUGCAGUUCUAGUACUUGUUCCUUGAAUAGCAGUGAAAACCCUUACGCCACAAUUAAGGACCCACCCAUCCUCACCUGCAAGCUUCCAGAAAGCAGCUAUGUAGAAAUGAAGUCGCCUGUGCACAUGGGGUCUCCGUACACAGAUGUGCCAUCCUUGUCGACAUCUAAUAAAAAUAUAUAUGAAGUUGGUAGGUGUCUCAAAUAAGUAACUUAGUGAAAUCAGGGCAAUAGUGCAGCAUUUGAAGUAAAAGCAAGCCCUCUCCACUCACCCCACCUUGACCACACAUCCUUCUUUUGUUGCUUUUAAAGGCAUCUCUAAGGUGAACUGUCUUUCCUAGGACUACCCUCCUAGCUAAUGCAGGAAGUCAAAUUAUUGUACCAACUCUGCUUUAAAAAACACCAGGACUAAUAUGAAACAAAUACUGGGGGUGGGAAAUGGGCACAUGCACGUGCACGCGCGCACACACACACACAGAUUGUUGAUACAAAUCUCAUUUUAAAAAAGAAAGCAAUCAGAGACAUCAACAAGUCUCUAAAUCACCUUCUACCUUCUCCCAGUUUAUGUCCCUGGGCUCACUGGUAAGACUCCUACCUCUAGGAUAUUUUAAAUCCUUUGGUGUUGAUGAGAGGCUUGGAUGUUGACAGCACAUUCACUUAGUUUUCCAUCUCCUGAGCAAGCCUCAGUCCUAACCCUCAUGUAUUUGCCAUAGAUUUAUAAAUCCCUGGCUCCUUUCCCCAAGUUAAGUAGAACUCUCUUCCUCUCCAACAAGGCAACCAAAGCUAAUCUGUUCUCUGAACUCAUUUUUCACUAUAUUUCUUAGAGCCCACAGUCAGUGUGGUCCAAGAAGGUUGCGGUCAUAACUCCAGCUAUAUCCAGAAUGCAUACGACCUACCUAGGAACAGCCAUAUUCCUGGUCAUUAUGACCUCCUCCCAGUAAGACAGAGCCCUGCCAAUGGGCCGUCCCAGGACAAGCAAUCUUAAGAGGGAUAAGCUUCUCUCUUGCAGUGUGCUCUACUGAAUAUUCUGACUCUGAAAGAAGACAGUCCCUUGACUUGAAGUAAUGGUACAGACUGGCUCCAGCUGCAUGUUAGUUAUUACGUUCACCUGGAACUAAAGAAGAGCGUCCAGGUGGGACUGGGAUAAUUGUUCAAGGAAUUGUGUUCUCAAAGGCAAAUCCUAUCACCCACUCAGCCCCAAAUGCCCUGGAUUAUAUGAUUUUUAAAACAUUUUAAGAUACAGCUACUCAUCAACAUCAGCUAAAUAUAGCUGAUAUAUAUAUAUAUAUUUAUCUGAAACGUGAUAUUUUAAAAACAUGUAGGUUUAACAAACCUUCCUAGGACAAAAAGGAGACUGGGGAGGGAAGAGGAUUACUUUAAAGCACCUGAAACGUAUAUGUACUUUUGGUUGCUGUUACCAUCAACAUCUGUUUUAUUACCGAAGACAAUUAGUACACAGACAUGAACUGUUCUUAAACAGAACAGUCUUAAAAUGUCUGUACAUAUCUGUCUGGUCCAUCAAAUUACAACAGCCAAGAUUACAGAAUCUAUAUAGUCUAAUGCUGACAACUUCUAUUUUAAAAAACAAGACUUUACUUUCUUCUGCCCCCUAAGUGAUAGGUUUAAACACACAGAGACACACACACACGUUUCCAAAGUGCAGCAGUGUCUCUUUCAGUCUACAAUAAGAUUCCUAGGGCAGCUUUAUCAAAUUUUGCCAAUUCAAAGUUCAAGGACAUUACAAGUUAGUCCUGGCUUUGUCAUAUCUACUUAGUCCAUCCGACACCUGAAUCAUUCCAUGUAAAACAGAGCUCUAAGAUGAUCCUUUAAGCAAGCAGUCAUAGACUGGUCGGGAUUAAGUAAAAGACGGCUAGUUGGCCUCCUCAUUUUAUUUGGUCAGCAUCCCUUGACUCAAGAGUACUUGCUUUCAAGUUCUUCAUAAAUCUUGAGAUUGACGUAGUAUGAAACCUAAAAGUAUACAGGAAAUUGGACAAAUGUGGAUACAGCAAGUUUACACUGCUUAAAGUACAUUAUGCUUUUUAAUGGAACUAAAUGAUCAAAAAAAGAAUGGACUGUAACCAGUUGCUGUAACGUGAUGUAAAAACGUUACUGUAAACAGCAUGAGGAUAUGAAGUCCUUCCACCUUCUAUCUUAAAACUACUACUUACUGAGCUAGCCCAAUAUGCAUUACAAUGAGCUAAUGCUCCAGAUCCCAGUAUUCAGAUGUGUCUAUACCUUCCACUAUGAACACAGAUAAACUGAGGCUCAGAUAAGUCCAAAUGAAAUGAAAUCAACUCCCAAGCCCUAAAGAGAACCUUCUCACAAGAAUUAAAAACAAAAAGGGCAAACCUAGGAAGCUAACGGCUACUCCUGUACCACUCUAUUCACUGGUACAGUCCAGCCAGUAAAAAACACUUCCAAAAAGAUACACAGAAGAGGAACUAAAUGACUGCGAAGCUGGAAUACUGCUACAGGAAGUAUGAGAGUUCUGAAACCCUUGAUAGAAACUGGAAGCCUGCCAUGGAACACAAUACUUUGGGCAAUAAUCAGAAAAAGCAAAAAAAUAAAUAAAUGAGUACAUCUCCCCUUCCCACAUCACUCAAGGCAUAAGCAGAUUUUACUGUUAGAGGAAAAUAUGUAAUACUUACAUGAAUGUUGCAUGUGUGCAUGGGAGCAACUGAGUAGCAAUAGUAAAUUUACUUUCCAAAAAAGCCUUAUUAAAAUAUAAAUAUUAGAAAAUUACUUUGGAGACCCAAGUAAAUAUUUCUCAUACAUAUGUAGAAAGAAAUAUAGGUAAGCAGCUUACCUCAGUAUUUCAGGGCAGCAAGUGUUUGUGAAGCAAGGAUGAGCAGCAUGAAGAUGUCAGAUCAGCAAGGAGAAACUUCAACUCAAUCCCAGGUUUUCUCUUCUUCCCUUAUCCUGCAUGUACAAUAACUGCUGCCUGGCAAACUGCAAACAAGCAGCAUCACUCAAGUUUGAAGUUUCGCCGCUUUUGUCAACUAUCCUCUGGGCAAAGGUAUUCAGCAAGAGGUGGAAUGGCUAGACACUGAAUCAAGAGAUUUCAGUGUUACUCUGGUCAAGUUAGUCGCCCUCUCUGGGCUCCCUUUUUUCCUAUGCAUAAAAAGGGGAGAAGCAGAGAGUGGGAAGACAGCUCUACUAACCCUUCAGCUCUAGCAGUCCAUGACUUUUUAAGGAAAUGUAAUACAAGUCAAACCAGGCAAUACAGAGGAGAAGGGAAAGGCAGAGGGUGUGAUUAUGGUGACAAUAGCUGCCUUCCCCUAUCGAACAGUUAUCAGUAAAAGACAUUUCAAUCUUACAAAGCAACUGUUAGAAACUUCUGUCUAACACCAUCACAAAUAGGUUCAUGGUCAGCCUAAACAUGUAUACUGUGCAUUUUAUGGGUGACUUUGAAAGAUCUGUUCAAUUAUUUUUCAGAAACUAAAUUUUCAAAAAAUUAAUAUGUGUACAAUUAAAAUGAAUGAAAGAAAAACCAUUAUUGUACAGAGGUAUUAAUGAGACUAUGAAACGGCAAUACUUUUUUAAAUCACAGAUUUGUAAUAUAUGUUCACUGUGCAGAGGGAUUGUACCUUGUACAAAAUAAAACAAAUUUCUCAAACUAA